UCCUCCAGAGCCUCAAGAGAUCUUUGGGCCAUAUCAGCUUUCUUUCCAAAAUGAACACACCCAGGGGCAGGAAAGAAUGCUCUUUCCUUGGUCAUUAAGGGGCCUGGGAGUCCUGGACCAGCUUUUCAUGCAGCUAGACCACUUACAUGCAACUAGAGCCUUGACUUUGAAACGAGGGACAAAAGCAUCUCUUGCUAAAGCCUCCUCACCACCAUCUGAUCUAUCUUGUUCUCUUCACAAAAGGCUCUGAAGACAUCAUGAACCCACAACGGGAGGCAGCACCCAAAUCCUAUGCUAUUCGUGAUUCUCGACAGAUGGUGUGGGUCCUGAGUGGAAAUUCUUUAAUAGCAGCUCCUCUUAGCCGCAGCAUUAAGCCUGUCACUCUUCAUUUAAUAGCCUGUAGAGACACAGAAUUCAGUGACAAGGAAAAGGGUAAUAUGGUUUACCUGGGAAUCAAGGGAAAAGAUCUCUGUCUCUUCUGUGCAGAAAUUCAGGGCAAGCCUACUUUGCAGCUUAAGGAAAAAAAUAUCAUGGACCUGUAUGUGGAGAAGAAAGCACAGAAGCCCUUUCUCUUUUUCCACAAUAAAGAAGGCUCCACUUCUGUCUUUCAGUCAGUCUCUUACCCUGGCUGGUUCAUAGCCACCUCCACCACAUCAGGACAGCCCAUCUUUCUCACCAAGGAGAGAGGCAUAACUAAUAACACUAACUUCUACUUAGAUUCUGUGGAAUAAAUCCAGCCUAGGCUGUGGGUGGCUGGUUCCAGGAUAGAGAAUCAAGCUGUCAGAGUCAUCUUAACAGAUCAUUAUGCGACUGAGUUCACUAGCAGUUCAGCCCAUCCAUAGCUUACCUCAUUCUUACUAUCCAAAAGCCACCUCCUCCUCCAAACAUCCAUUUCUGUACCAAGACCCUCACUCGAAUGUCACUAUCCCAAGAUGAAACCUAAAAAUCACUUUCCAUUCUUUCUUGAUCUUACCCCACCAUCCACUCAGCUGCCAUGCCCAGUUUAGUCAACCCCCCAAAUGCUGCUUCAUGCAACCUUCCAUUCCUAUUCCUUUUGCCAACCCAUGAUGUAGAGAUGUGGAUUCAUGACAUUUUGUUCAUACAACUUCUUCAAUAAAACAUUAUAAUAUGUGCCCCAAAGAUAAAGCUGAAGAAUGAGAUGAAUGUGAAAUUAAAGGUUUGCAUGUCUUUCUAAUCCUAA